ACUCUGCCAAAGUCGCAGUACAGAUUCCGAAGCCGCAGCGCCGUCCCCUCCUUUCCUCGCCCCAGCCCGAGCGGGAAGCGGCAGCAGCUCCCCAGAGCCCUGGCUUGGCAGGGAGGGGACGGCGCCCGAGCAGCCAUAUUGCAGCCCCCCGGGUCCCUCCUCCGGCCGGCGCAGGCCCCGCGCUCACGACCUCCUCUGGGAGCCGGAUCUGUCCUCUCCAUCGCCGCCACCCGCCGGCCUCUGCGUCCCUUGGCUUCCGACAUCCCGUCUGGCCGUCCCCCUGUGCCGGUCCGAGCCUCUGUUUAUUUCCUUUCCUACUAUCAAUACUCGACCAGCAGAAAAGGAAAGUUUAAAAAUGCCAAUCGCACAGUUGCUGGAACUAUGGAAAAAGAUCGAGGUGGAGCCUAUGGAAAUAGAGACCACAGAGGAGGAUCUCAACCUGGAUGUGGAGCCCACCACAGAAGACACUGCAGAAGAAGGCAAAAGUGACUCAGCUGCCUGCAAGACAAAGGUAGCUGGAUCCGUAGAGGAAGAAGGCGUCGUGAAGGAGAUAGACAUCAGCCAUCAUGUGAAGGAGGGCUUUGAGAAGGCAGAUCCUUCCCAGUUUGAGCUGCUGAAGGUUUUAGGACAAGGAUCCUAUGGAAAGGUGUUCCUGGUGAGGAAGGUGAAGGGGUCCGACGCUGGGCAGCUCUACGCCAUGAAGGUCCUUAAGAAAGCCACCCUAAAAGUUCGGGACCGAGUGAGAUCGAAGAUGGAGAGAGACAUCUUGGCAGAAGUGAAUCACCCCUUCAUUGUGAAGCUUCAUUAUGCCUUUCAGACGGAAGGAAAGCUCUACCUGAUCCUGGACUUCCUGCGGGGAGGGGACCUCUUCACCCGGCUCUCCAAAGAGGUCAUGUUCACGGAGGAGGAUGUCAAGUUCUACCUGGCUGAGCUGGCCUUGGCUUUAGACCAUCUCCACAGCCUGGGGAUCAUCUACAGAGAUCUGAAGCCUGAGAACAUCCUCCUGGAUGAAGAGGGGCACAUUAAGAUCACAGAUUUCGGCCUGAGUAAGGAGGCCAUUGACCACGACAAGAGAGCGUACUCCUUCUGCGGGACGAUCGAGUACAUGGCGCCCGAGGUGGUGAACCGGCGAGGACACACGCAGAGUGCCGACUGGUGGUCCUUCGGCGUGCUCAUGUUUGAGAUGCUCACGGGGUCCCUGCCGUUCCAGGGGAAGGACAGGAAGGAGACCAUGGCUCUCAUCCUCAAAGCCAAGCUGGGGAUGCCGCAGUUCCUCAGUGGGGAGGCACAGAGUUUGCUGCGAGCUCUCUUCAAACGGAACCCCUGCAACCGGCUGGGUGCUGGCAUUGACGGAGUGGAGGAAAUUAAGCGCCAUCCCUUCUUUGUGACCAUAGACUGGAACACGCUGUACCGGAAGGAGAUCAAGCCACCGUUCAAACCAGCAGUGGGCAGGCCUGAGGACACCUUCCACUUUGACCCCGAGUUCACAGCGCGGACGCCCACAGACUCUCCUGGCGUCCCCCCGAGUGCAAACGCUCAUCACCUGUUUAGAGGAUUCAGCUUUGUGGCCUCAAGCCUGAUCCAGGAGCCCUCACAGCAAGAUCUGCACAAAGUCCCAGUUCACCCAAUCGUGCAGCAGUUACACGGGAACAACAUCCACUUCACCGAUGGCUACGAGAUCAAGGAGGACAUCGGGGUGGGCUCCUACUCAGUGUGCAAGCGAUGUGUGCAUAAAGCCACAGACACCGAGUAUGCCGUGAAGAUCAUUGAUAAGAGCAAGAGAGACCCCUCGGAAGAGAUUGAGAUCCUCCUGCGGUACGGCCAGCACCCGAACAUCAUCACCCUCAAGGAUGUCUAUGAUGAUGGCAAGUUUGUGUACCUGGUAAUGGAGCUGAUGCGUGGUGGGGAGCUCCUGGACCGCAUCCUCCGGCAGAGAUACUUCUCGGAGCGCGAAGCCAGUGACGUCCUGUGCACCAUCACCAAGACCAUGGACUACCUCCAUUCCCAGGGGGUUGUUCAUCGAGACCUGAAGCCGAGUAACAUCCUGUACAGGGAUGAGUCGGGGAGCCCAGAAUCCAUCCGAGUCUGCGACUUCGGCUUUGCCAAGCAGCUGCGCGCGGGGAACGGGCUGCUCAUGACACCCUGCUACACGGCCAAUUUCGUGGCCCCGGAGGUCCUGAAGCGUCAAGGCUAUGAUGCGGCGUGUGACAUCUGGAGUUUGGGGAUCCUGUUGUACACCAUGCUGGCAGGAUUUACCCCUUUUGCAAAUGGGCCAGACGAUACCCCUGAGGAGAUUCUGGCGCGGAUCGGCAGUGGGAAGUAUGCCCUUUCUGGGGGAAACUGGGACUCGAUAUCUGACGCAGCUAAAGACGUCGUGUCCAAGAUGCUCCACGUGGACCCUCAUCAGCGCCUGACGGCGAUGCAAGUGCUCAAACACCCGUGGGUGGUCAACAGAGAGUACCUGUCCCCAAACCAGCUCAGCCGACAGGACGUGCACCUGGUGAAGGGCGCGAUGGCCGCCACCUACUUUGCUCUAAACAGAACACCUCAGGCCCCGCGGCUGGAGCCCGUGCUGUCAUCCAACCUGGCUCAGCGCAGAGGCAUGAAGAGACUCACGUCCACGCGGCUGUAGCGGGUGGGACCCUGGCCCCAGCGUCCCCUGCCAGCAUCCUCGUGGGCUCACAGACCCCGGCCUCGGAGCCCGUCUGGCACCCAGAGUGACCACAAGUCCAGCAGGGAGGCGGCGCCCGCCCUCGCCGUGUCCGUGUUUUCUUUUUCAGCCCCGGAGAGGGUCCUGACCUGGGGGCUUCUCCAAGCCUCACUGCGCCAGCCUCCCCGCCCGCUCUCUUUUCUCCCAAGCGAAACCAAAUGCGCCCCUUCACCUCGCGUGCCCGUGCGAGGCCGGGGGCUUCUUUCAGAGCCCGCGGGUCCUCUCAUACAUGGCUUCUGUUUCUGCCGAGAGAUCUGUUUUCCAAUUAUGAAGCCGGUCGGUUUGGUCAGACUCCCGACACCCACGUCCCAGGUACCCGGUGGGAAAGUGGCAGUGCGAGGGCGCAGCCAUUGGUGGUUGCAGGGCCCCAGAGGGCUGGGGUGACCUGGCAUCCCGGGGCUCCCCACGGGCUGGAUGACGGGGUUGGCACUGUGGCGUCCAGGAGGAGAUGCCUGGUUCUGCCCAAAAUAAUCCAAAGAGCCGUUUCCUCCUCGCCCUUCAGUUUUUGCCUGAGGUGCUGGGUAGCCCAUCCUUUCCUCUGUCCCAGAUUCAAAUGAGGAGUAAGAGCCCAGACGAGAGGAAGGCAGGCUGGAUCUUUGCCUUGAGAGCUCCGUGUCACCAGGAUGGAAGGGGGUGCCUCUCGGAGGAGCCUGUGUCCACCUCCAGUCUCGGCUUUCCCCGGGGGGCCAAGCGCACUGGGCUGCCGUCUGUCCCCAGCUCCCGUGGCCACACAGCUAUCUGGAGGCUUUGCAGGGAGUCGUGGGUUCUCGCACCUGCUCAGCCCUGUGUCGGCUUCCUGUGUGCUCACCUAAAGCUGUGGUUUUGCUGUGUUCACUUCGAUUUUUCUGGUCUGUGGAGAAACUGUGAAUUGGAGAAAUGGAGCUCUGUGGCUUCCCACCCAAACCUUCUCAGUCCAGCUGGAGGCUGGAGGGAGACACAGGCCCCACCCAGCAGACUGAGGGGCAGAGGCACAGGUGGGAGGGCAGCGGAGAUCAGCGUGGACAGGAGCGAUGCACUUUGUAGAUGCUGUGGCUUUGUGUUGCGUUUUGUGUCUCUGUUGCACAGAUCUGUUUUUUCACACUGAUCCGUAUUCCCCUGGGUGUGCACACAGGGCGGGUGUGGGGCAUUUAGGCCAUGCUGUGCUCUACUUCAUUGAGUAAAAUCGAGUGAGAGGUUCCGGGCAGCAGGAUCGACGCCCAGUCCAGCCGGCAGAGGGAACACACGGGUCCUUCAUUGUCCUGUAAGGGUGUUGAAGAUGCUCCCUGGCGGCCCCCAAGCAGACUAGAUGGGAGGAGGCGCCGCUCAGCCCCUCACCCUGCAUCACUGAAGAGCGGCGCCUCUGCAGCAAGCAGGGCUUCAGGAGGUGCCCGCUGGCCACAGCCAGGUUUUCCCUAAGAAGAUGUUAUUUUGUUGGGUUUUGUUCCCCCUCCAUCUCGAUUCUCGUACCCAACUAAAAAAAAAAAAAUAAAGAAAAAAUGUGCUGCGUUCUGAAAAAUAACUCCUUAGCUUGGUCUGAUUGUUUUCAGACCUUAAAAUAUAAACUUGUUUCACAAGCUUUAAUCCAUGUGGAUUUUUUUUUUCUUAGAGAACCACAAAACAUAAAAGGAGCAAGUCGGACUGAAUACCUGUUUCCAUAGUGCCCACAGGGUAUUCCUCACAUUUUCUCCAUAGAAGAUGCUUUUUCCCAAGGCUAGAACGACUUCCACCAUGAUGAAUUUGCUUUUUAGGUCUUAAUUAUUUCACUUCUUUUUAGAAACUUAGGAAGAAGUGGAUAAUCCUGAGGUCACACAAUCUGUCCUCCCAGAAAUGAACAAAAGUCAUCACCUUUUCUGCUUGCUACACAGGCAACGAUUCCCCCAUCAGCUGCCCGGACCCUUUGGCCUGGCUUGGUGUGCAGGCCUGUCUGUUUGCUUAAAGUCAGUGGGUUCUGGUGCAGGGAGUGAGAAGUGGGGGAAGUGAAAGGGAAAGCAUCCGUGAGAAAGCGGCCACGGUUUUCCCUCCUUGUGUGCCCAUGGGGCACCAGCUCAUGGUCUUUUUCAGUCAUCCCAGUUUGUACAGACUUAGCUUCUGAACUCUAAGAAUGCCAAAGGGACCGACGAGACUCCCCAUCACAGCGAGCUCUGUCCUUACAUGUAUUUGAUGUGCAUCAGCGGAGGAGAACACUGGCUUGGCCCUGCUCCGCUGAGUGUCUGUGAAAUACCUCUACUUUCCCUCCCAUAUCCAGAACAAAAUGAUACUUGACAUCCUUCCACAAAAGUCAGCCUAAAGAAGUUAUGGUAUCAUAUGUUAAACUAAGCUUUCAAAAACCUUAGUGAAAUAGCAAGUGACUGCUUUCAAGCAGCAGUCGACAUGUAAAUGAAGGUGUUCUUAGAAUUCGCAUUUUGCCAGCUCAGCGCACCUCCACAACGAAUGAAAUGCUCCGUAUGAUUUGCACAAAUGACAUAGACCUCCCCAAAAGUUAACUGGCUCUCCUUCCUCACACAGUUCAUCAUAACCCAACCCCCCACCCCCGGGUCAUGAAAAUCACAGAACUUAUAAACACAUUGAACCCUAGAUCUCAGGCUUCCUGACCUACCGCCAGUGGCCCCUUGCUGGCCACCCUAUAGGGUCCUCCUUCCCUGGCAGCCCCCCAUGUGGGAGAAAUACCUGAUUCUCCCAAUCUGCAGUGGGAGAGCUUUGCUGAAUUCCAUCCCAAAGUCAAACAUGGGCAAGAGGUGAGGAUUUCACUUUUACCCUCAAGUCCGAUUUGUCUGUGAUUUUAAACUAACUGUGUAUGUAUUGAUGUUUGGAAGAUUGUUUGAAUUUUAAAGUGAUAAUAGUACUUAAUGUUAUCCAGUAUUGUUCAUUAAAUGGUGUUAUCCUAAAGCUGCACUUGGGAUUUUUACCUAACGCUUUACUGAUUCUCUCAAGCACAUGGCAAAGUUUGAUUUGCACUCCGUUCAUUUCUGACACGUUUUGCUGCCUCCUACCUUUCUAAGCGUCAUGCAAAUUCGAGAAUGGAGAAGGACGCUGCCGGUCCCUGAGCGGUGUGGAGAGGGCGGAAGGUGGACUCCAGCGCAGCUUGAGGGGCUGAGGACGGAGGCUGCAGCAUCUGUGUCGUUCUACUGAGCACGCUUCUCUGCCUCGCUCCUGACUCAGCACUUUGUUCACUGGCUCAGCAGUUAUGUUUACACAUCAUUUUUAUGUUCCUGCUUUGUAAUUCAUGUUUGAGAUGGGUGGCCACUGUACAGAUAUUUAUUACGCUUUCCAGACUUUCUGAAUAGAUUUUUUUGAAUAAACAUGGUUUUAUGAAGUGUAAUCUUUUUCUAGCCUAACAAUAA